GAGCCGGUCCGGUGUGUGCAGGGGAGCGCCUCGCCAGCGGUCCGCAGGGCUGGAGACCCACGCCGUGGAGAGGACCAGCCUCAGGUCGCCCCGCCUGGGCCCGCGCCCCGACCUCGCUGCCCCCGCCUCGCCUCUCUGCCCGUGGCGCUUACGGCCACCUUGGCCUCGGGGGCAGGGCAUGGGCGGCCCCCGCCAGAUCGCCCAGCGCCAGUACUAACUGCCCUCGCUCUGGCCUUCGAGCCCGAAGCCUCUUCUGCGCGCACAACCUAGGCAGUAAUCCUAAACUAGCGGGCACCACAGACCAGCUGCAGCCACCCCAACCCAGGGAUCACUUCCGGACCCCUCGACCGCCCGGCACCAGCGCGCAAGGGACCCUUCAGCCGGAGACCAGAGUCCAGUCCCGGUCACGAGGCCACCGCCGCUGCCCGCCUCGAGAAGCACCACGCGGGCUGAGCCGUCGGCUAGCGGGUCACUCCCGAGCCUCUGUCUGCACCGCGCCAGCCCCAGACCACGGACGCUGAGCCUCCAGCGCGUGCCAGCCUGGGCCGCUGGGCUCUCGGGGCCAGCCCGCGACGAUCCCCUGAGCUCUCCGCAGAAGGGCCGAGCGUCCGUUCCGGGGACGCCAGGCCCGCCCCCGCCCCCCGACAGCCGCGGGGAUCCAGAGCCCGGGGGUGCGGGACGCCCGCGCCAUGACUGCCGAGAGCGGGCCGCCGCCGCCGCAGCCGGAGGUGCUGGCUACCGUGAAGGAAGAGCGCGGCGAGACGGCAGCAGGGGCCGGGGUCCCAGGGGAGGCCACGGGCCGCGGGGCGGGCGGGCGGCGCCGCAAGCGCCCCCUGCAGCGCGGGAAGCCGCCCUACAGCUACAUCGCGCUCAUCGCCAUGGCCAUCGCGCACGCGCCCGAGCGCCGCCUCACGCUGGGCGGCAUCUACAAGUUCAUCACCGAGCGCUUCCCCUUCUACCGCGACAACCCCAAAAAGUGGCAGAACAGCAUCCGCCACAACCUCACACUCAACGACUGCUUCCUCAAGAUCCCGCGCGAGGCCGGCCGCCCGGGUAAGGGCAACUACUGGGCGCUUGACCCCAACGCGGAGGACAUGUUCGAGAGCGGCAGCUUCCUGCGCCGCCGCAAGCGCUUCAAGCGCUCGGACCUCUCCACCUACCCGGCUUACAUGCACGACGCGGCGGCUGCCGCAGCCGCCGCCGCCGCCGCCGCCGCCGCCGCCGCCAUCUUCCCAGGCGCGGUGCCCGCCGCGCGCCCCCCCUACCCGGGCGCCGUCUAUGCAGGCUACGCGCCGCCGUCGCUGGCCGCGCCGCCUCCAGUCUACUACCCCGCGGCGUCGCCCGGCCCUUGCCGCGUCUUCGGCCUGGUUCCUGAGCGGCCGCUCAGCCCAGAGCUGGGGCCCGCACCGUCGGGGCCCGGCGGCUCUUGCGCCUUUGCCUCCGCCGGCGCCCCCGCUACCACCACCGGCUACCAGCCCGCAGGCUGCACCGGGGCCCGGCCGGCCAACCCCUCCGCCUAUGCGGCUGCCUACGCGGGCCCCGACGGCGCGUACCCGCAGGGCGCCGGCAGUGCGAUCUUUGCCGCUGCUGGCCGCCUGGCGGGACCCGCUUCGCCCCCAGCGGGCGGCAGCAGUGGCGGCGUGGAGACCACGGUGGACUUCUACGGGCGCACGUCGCCCGGCCAGUUCGGAGCGCUGGGAGCCUGCUACAACCCUGGCGGGCAGCUCGGAGGGGCCAGUGCAGGCGCCUACCAUGCUCGCCAUGCUGCCGCUUAUCCCGGUGGGAUAGAUCGGUUCGUGUCCGCCAUGUGAGCCAGCGUAGGGACGAAAACUCAUAGACACAUCGGCUGUUCACACGUUCCCCGCAAUCUGAGAACGAACAGGAAUGGAGAGAGGACUCAACUGGGACCCACGUGGAAAAGACCGAGCAGGCCACAGAGGCUCGGUCUCCCCGCGCACAGCGUAGGCACCCGGUGUACUCUGUAAACGGGAGGAGGUGGGGCGAGGCAGCCAGAGCCCUUGGACUGGCACAGGGACCCUCGAUGGAGCGAAGCCCUCAAACGGGAUGCUUUCUGGUAUUCUAUCGGGGAGGGUCCUUGGCGGUAACCAGAGGGCAGCGUAGUGUCAACACCAGAGACCAGGAUCCAAAUUGUGGGGAAUCAGUUUCAGCCUUCCAUGUGCUGCCGGAACUCGGGCCUUUUUACGCGGUUCGUCCUCUAGUGCCUUUAACUGCGUUACUACAAUAAAAGGCUGCGGCAGCGCCUUUCUUCUUAAAGUGAGGAGGACAAAUUUGCAAAAGAAAUAGGCUUUUCUUCUUUUUUAAAUUGGAGAAAUCUCUGCUCUGGUUGACCUGGGCUGGUUUUCCCUGUCUCUGAGAACUUGAGACCUAGCUCCGAGUUGAACUGUGCGUCAGCACUCCAGUCCCAUCACCUGAACCUUCAGUCUCCCCCAUCUGUUACACUAGAGGGCUGCAGGACUCUAUCCACCGCCCCCGGGUUAUCAUUCAGGGCCCCAUCAUCUUGGAUGCUGCCCUGCGUAUUUGGCAGCAAUGGUGGGCCACCCAGGGCCUCUGAGUAGCCACCCAAAGCCUAGCCGCUGUUCUAGGGAACGGAAAAGAGUUCAUGGCCAAGCGUCUAACCUAAAGUCCCAGGAUUGGCUCCAGGCAGCAAUUAUAUCAUAACUUAUUGAACUUUUGAGCAGGACGUGCUGGUAAUUUCAUGGCUGUUACUGCCCAGUCAUAAAUCUGCUUUUCCAUUAUAAGGCAGAGAGAAGUACAUUCGUUCAUUUGUCCACUGUUUCUUGUCAUCACGCAGCCCUGGACCCAAAGGGUGAACUAAAGUUUAAGGAGAUGAGAGGAUUCAAGGAGCCCGUUGGUGACGCCUUUCAGUAGCUGGGGAGGGCUCUUCCAUCCCCAGCACCCCCUGCUACACCUCAGCAGCCUCCCCCAUGCAAAAAGGAAAGAGAAAAAUUAAGUUAGGGCAGUCAGUAAAGUGAGCUUUAGAAAGAAACUGGAAUUUUAACUUCAUUUUGUAUCUUGCUUAAGUAGCAGGCUCACUAAAAUUAGAGAAAGUCCAAUAACUCUCCCCCUUUCCCUUGAGAAAUCUUUAAGUUUCGAUUCUGGAGCAAAAACUUUCAGCAUUAAAUAUUUCAGAGGCUCCAUUCACAGCUUUCAGAUAAACUGGAGUGUUCAGAUGGACUGUUUUAAUAAAAAUCUUUGAGCAAGUGAGUUAUGGCAAGAGAAACUCAGCCUCUUUCUGUAUAAACUUAACAGGGAAGGGCUGGGGUGUGAAAAAGAAGAUUGUAUGAAAACCAUUGGUAAUUUUUAUUUUUUAUUUUUGGGACUGCACUAUCCUGUUCACGAAGACAUGUGAACUUGGUUCAGUCCAAAUGGGGAUUUGUAUAAACCAGUGCUCUCCAUUAGAAAUAUGGUGCAAGCCACAUAUGUAAUUUUAAAUAUUCUAGUAGCCACAUUAAUAAAGUAAAAAGAAACAGG